AAUCCGGAUUCUCAGGGCUUCAACUACACAAGCCCCACAAACCGGCUGCUGGGCUGCAGGGAAGCUCACUCCAGAAUUUAAAGUGCCCAGGCUACAGAGACACCCUGAAGCCACAGAAAGACAAAGGAACCGGUUGAAACACACAACGUGUCCAGUGAGGACUUUGCAGAAUUCUGUAACCAGACUACAAUGGCCGCUCAAAGGAAUCGCUCAAAGGAAUCAAAGGAUUGCAGCGGGCUGGUCCUGCUCUGCCUUUUCUUCGGGAUUCCAUGGGAGGCUGGAGCCCGGCAGAUCUCCUACUCAAUUCCUGAGGAAUUAGAGAAAGGCUCUUUCGUGGGCAACAUCUCCAAGGACUUGGGUCUGGCGCCCCGGGAGCUGGCGGAGCGCGGAGUCCGCAUAGUCUCCAGAGGUAGGACGCAGCUUUUCUCUCUGAACCCGCGCAGCGGCAGCUUGAUCACCGCGGGCAGGAUAGACCGGGAGGAGCUCUGCGCUCAGAGCGCGCGGUGCGUGGUGAGUUUUAAUAUCCUUGUGGAAGACAGGGUGAAACUUUUUGGGAUAGAAAUAGAAGUAACUGAUAUCAAUGACAAUGCUCCAAAAUUCCAAGCAGAAAAUCUAGACGUAAAAAUUAAUGAAAAUGUCGCUGCGGGAAUGCGUUUUCCUCUCCCGGAAGCUAUUGAUCCGGAUGUGGGCGUGAACUCCCUGCAGAGCUAUCAGCUCAGCCCCAAUAAGCACUUCUCCCUAAGAGUUCAGAGCCGUGCCAAUGGCGUCAAGUACCCGGAGCUGGUACUGGAGCACUCCCUAGAUCGCGAGGAAGAGGCCAUUCACCACCUGGUCCUCACCGCCUCCGACGGGGGUGACCCUCUCCGAUCUGGCACUGUCCUUGUCAGUGUGACUGUCUUCGAUGCAAAUGACAACGCGCCGGUCUUCACCUUGCCAGAAUACCGAGUGAGUGUUCCUGAGAAUUUGCCUGUGGGCACUCAGCUGCUGACAGUCACAGCCACCGACAGGGACGAAGGUGCCAAUGGAGAAGUGACAUAUUCAUUCCGAAAAUUACCUGACACGCAAUUGUUGAAGUUCCAACUAAACAAAUAUACUGGAGAAAUAAAAAUAUCAGAAAAUCUAGAUUAUGAAGAAACCGGUUUCUAUGAAAUAGAAAUACAAGCAGAAGAUGGAGGAGCAUAUCUUGCAACUGCAAAAGUGUUGAUUACAGUAGAAGAUGUAAAUGACAACAGUCCAGAGCUGACCAUCACGUCUCUAUUUAGUCCAGUGACUGAAGAUUCACCUCUGGGAACAGUCGUAGCCCUUUUAAAUGUGCAUGAUUUAGACUCUGAGCAGAAUGGACAGGUAACCUGUUCCAUUUUGGCGUAUCUACCAUUUAAAUUAGAAAAGUCCAUUGACAGUUAUUACAGAUUGGUGAUACACAGAGCCCUUGACAGGGAACAGGUAUCCUCUUACAAUAUCACAGUGACAGCCACAGAUGGGGGAAGUCCUCCUCUAUCAACGGAAGCUCACUUUAUGCUACAAGUGGCAGAUAUCAAUGACAACCCACCUACCUUCUCUCAAGUCUCCUACUUUACCUAUAUCCCAGAGAACAACGCCAGGGGUGCCUCCAUCUUCUCAGUGACAGCGCUGGACCCGGACAGCAAAGAGAAUGCCCAGAUUAUUUACUCCCUGGCUGAAGACACCAUCCAGGGGGUACCUCUGUCCUCAUACAUAUCCAUCAACUCAGACACUGGCGUCCUGUAUGCACUCAGAUCCUUCGACUAUGAGCAGUUUCAUGAGCUACAGAUGCAGGUGACAGCCAGCGACAGCGGGGAUCCUCCACUCAGCAGCAACGUGUCGUUGAGCCUGUUUGUGCUGGACCAGAACGACAAUGCGCCCGAGAUCCUGUACCCCGCCCUCCCCACAGACGGUUCCACAGGCGUGGAGCUGGCGCCCCGCUCCGCAGAGCCCGGCUACCUGGUGACCAAGGUGGUGGCGGUGGACAGAGACUCCGGCCAGAACGCCUGGCUGUCCUACCGUCUGCUCAAGGCCAGCGAGCCGGGACUCUUCGCGGUGGGGGAGCACACGGGCGAGGUGCGCACGGCGCGAGCCCUGCUGGACAGAGACGCGCUCAAGCAAAGCCUCGUAGUGGCCGUCCAGGACCACGGCCAGCCCCCUCUCUCCGCCACUGUCACGCUCACCGUGGCCGUGGCCGACAGCAUCCCCCAAGUCCUGGCGGACCUCGGCAGCUUCGAGUCUCCAGCUAACUCUGAAACCUCAGACCUCACUCUGUACCUGGUGGUAGCGGUGGCCGCGGUCUCCUGCGUCUUCCUGGCCUUCGUCAUCGUGCUGCUGGCGCACAGGCUGCGGCGCUGGCACAAGUCACGCCUGCUGCAGGCUUCAGGAGGCGGCUUGACAGGUGUGUCCGGCUCGCACUUUGUGGGCGUGGACGGGGUUCGGGCUUUCCUGCAGACCUAUUCCCACGAGGUCUCUCUCACCGCGGACUCGCGAAAGAGUCACCUGAUCUUCCCCCAGCCCAAUUAUGCGGACACGCUCAUCAGCCAGGAGAGCUGUGAGAAAAACGAUCCUUUGUCUUUGUUAGAUGAUUCGAAGUUUCCUAUAGAGGAUACCCCAUUGGUUCCACAAGCCCCGCCCAACACGGACUGGCGUUUCUCUCAGGCCCAGAGACCCGGCACCAGCGGCUCCCAAAAUGGCGAUGACACCGGCACCUGGCCCAACAACCAGUUUGACACAGAGAUGCUGCAAGCCAUGAUCUUGGCGUCCGCCAGUGAAGCUGCUGAUGGGAGCUCCACCCUGGGAGGGGGUGCCGGCACCAUGGGAUUGAGCGCCCGCUACGGACCCCAGUUCACCCUGCAGCACGUGCCCGACUACCGCCAGAAUGUCUACAUCCCAGGCAGCAAUGCCACACUGACCAACGCAGCUGGCAAGCGGGAUGGCAAGGCCCCAGCAGGUGGCAAUGGCAACAAGAAGAAGUCGGGCAAGAAGGAGAAGAAGUAACAUGGAGGCCAGGCCAAGAGCCACAGGGCGGCCUCUCCCCAACCAGCCCAGCUUCUCCUUACCUGCACCCAGGCCUCAGAGUUUCAGGGCUAACCCCCAGAAUACUGGUAGGGGCCAAGGCCAUGCUCCCCUUGGGAAACAGAAACAAGUGCCCAGUCAGCACCUACCCCUUCCCCCCCAGGGGGUUGAAUAUGCAAAAGCAGUUCCGCUGGGAACCCCCAUCCAAUCAACUGCUGUACCCAUGGGGGUAGUGGGGUUACUGUAGACACCAAGAACCAUUUGCCACACCCCGUUUAGUUACAGCUGAACUCCUCCAUCUUCCAAAUCAAUCAGGCCCAUCCAUCCCAUGCCUCCCUCCUCCCCACCCCACUCCAACAGUUCCUCUUUCCCGAGUAAGGUGGUUGGGGUGUUGAAGUACCAAGUAACCUACAAGCCUCCUAGUUCUGAAAAGUUGGAAGGGCAUCAUGACCUCUUGGCCUCUCCUUUGAUUCUCAAUCUUCCCCCAAAGCAUGGUUUGGUGCCAGCCCCUUCACCUCCUUCCAGAGCCCAAGAUCAAUGCUCAAGUUUUGGAGGACAUGAUCACCAUCCCCAUGGUACUGAUGCUUGCUGGAUUUAGGGAGGGCAUUUUGCUACCAAGCCUCUUCCCAACGCCCUGGGGACCAGUCUUCUGUUUUGUUUUUCAUUGUUUGACGUUUCCACUGCAUGCCUUGACUUCCCCCACCUCCUCCUCAAACAAGAGACUCCACUGCAUGUUCCAAGACAGUAUGGGGUGGUAAGAUAAGGAAGGGAAGUGUGUGGAUGUGGAUGGUGGGGGCAUGGACAAAGCUUGACACAUCAAGUUAUCAAGGCCUUGGAGGAGGCUCUGUAUGUCCUCAGGGGACUGACAACAUCCUCCAGAUUCCAGCCAUAAACCAAUAACUAGGCUGGACCCUUCCCACUACAUAAUAGGGCUCAGCCCAGGCAGCCAGCUUUGGGCUGAGCUAACAGGACCAAUGGAUUAAACUGGCAUUUCAGUCCAAGGAAGCUCGAAGCAGGUUUAGGACCAGGUCCCCUUGAGAGGUCAGAGGGGCCUCUGUGGGUGCUGGGUACUCCAGAGGUGCCACUGGUGGAAGGGUCAGCGGAGCCCCAGCAGGAAGGGUGGGCCAGCCAGGCCAUUCUUAGUCCCUGGGUUGGGGAGGCAGGGAGCUAGGGCAGGGACCAAAUGAACAGAAAGUCUCAGCCCAGGAUGGGGCUUCUUCAACAGGGCCCCUGCCCUCCUGAAGCCUCAGUCCUUCACCUUGCCAGGUGCCGUUUCUCUUCCGUGAAGGCCACUGCCCAGGUCCCCAGUGCGCCCCCUAGUGGCCAUAGCCUGGUUAAAGUUCCCCAGUGCCUCCUUGUGCAUAGACCUUCUUCUCCCACCCCCUUCUGCCCCUGGGUCCCCGGCCAUCCAGCGGGGCUGCCAGAGAACCCCAGACCUGCCCUUACAGUAGUGUAGCGCCCCCUCCCUCUUUCGGCUGGUGUAGAAUAGCCAGUAGUGUAGUGCGGUGUGCUUUUACGUGAUGGCGGGUGGGCAGCGGGCGGCGGGCUCCGCGCAGCCGUCUGUCCUUGAUCUGCCCGCGGCGGCCCGUGUUGUGUUUUGUGCUGUGUCCACGCGCUAAGGCGACCCCCUCCCCCGUACUGACUUCUCCUAUAAGCGCUUCUCUUCGCAUAGUCACGUAGCUCCCACCCCACCCUCUUCCUGUGUCUCACGCAAGUUUUAUACUCUAAUAUUUAUAUGGCUUUUUUUCUUCGACAAAAAAAUAAUAAAACGUUUCUUCUGAAAA